AUGUAUUUCAUUUGCUUAAAUGACCUAAGAUUCCCUAAGAACAAGACUGAGCUUUAUUUCCCAGUCAAAAAGAAGCAUGAGUGGGCCAACUCAGCCACUGGGAAGAAGAGGAGGUGGAGAAAGAAGAGGAGGAAGGAAGCCUAUUUUAGUUACAUGGGGAAAAUCCUAAAGCAAAUCCACCCUGAUUUCAGCGGGCGUUCCUGGGUCUUGUAUGCACUAGGUGCCCUCAAUGCUUGGCAACUGGAAUGGGUUAGCCUGGAGGCAUUUAGGCUGUCCUUCUACAACCACAGAAGAGCCAUCACUGGCAGAGAGAUCCUUGGCGCAGUUAAGCAGAGAUCUUCUCAGAAGAGCUUUUGAAUAAAUGAAGUUGUUCAGAAUGGCCUUGUUAAAAUGACUCACUUGUCAAAAAACUAGAUGUGUUGGAAGGCUGGGUUGGAAGACAAGAUGUCUGAGAAGCUGUCCUGCUGCAUGAGGAGUUUCAUUGCUACACACCUAGUCUCUGGGUCCUGUGUUUUUGGCCUCCAGCUUACUUCGUGAACAUAAUAAAGGAAAGGCAUUUUCUCUUGUGCA